AUGUUGGGCCAGGCGUGGUGGCUCAUGCCUCUGGGGCGAGGGGAUAGGCCGAGUUCCGGGUGUAAGGGGGCCAUUAGGGAGAGCAGAGCGAGGCAGCUGAUCUUCCGGAUUGGGGGCCUUGCCCGGAAGCUGGACCUCACGGAGAUGAAACGGAAGAUGCACGAGGAUAUGAUCUCCAUACAGAACUUUCUCAUCUACGUGGCCCUGCUGCGAGUCACUCCAUUUAUCUUAAAGAAAUUGGACAGCAUAUGAAGAUUGGACAUCACAUGUGAAUGCAUGAUAUGAAGAGCCUGGUUACAGUUUCUACUGUUCUCUGCAAGUAAAUAGGCCCAGAAAGGUAUAAGAGACUCUUUGAAUGGACAUAAAAAUUCUGCUUGUUAAGAACAAGUUGAGCUCUGGUAACUGAUCUUAAUAGCUAAAAUAUAAAAAUAUUUGGGAAGUCUGAAA